CCCCUUCUCCCCGGCGGUUAGUGCUGAGAGUGCGGAGUGUGUGCUCCGGGCUCGGAACACACAUUUAUUAUUAAAAAAUCCAAAAAAAAUCUAAAAAAAUCUUUUAAAAAACCCCAAAAAAAUUUACAAAAAAUCCGCGUCUCCCCCGCCGGAGACUUUUAUUUUUUUUCUUCCUCUUUUAUAAAAUAACCCGGUGAAGCAGCCGAGACCGACCCGCCCGCCCGCGGCCCCGCAGCAGCUCCAAGAAGGAACCAAGAGACCGAGGCCUUCCCGCUGCCCGGACCCGACACCGCCACCCUCGCUCCCCGCCGGCAGCCGGCAGCCAGCGGCAGUGGAUCGACCCCGUUCUGCGGCCGUUGAGUAGUUUUCAAUUCCGGUUGAUUUUUGUCCCUCUGCGCUUGCUCCCCGCUCCCCUCCCCCCGGCUCCGGCCCCCAGCCCCGGCACUCGCUCUCCUCCUCUCACGGAAAGGUCGCGGCCUGUGGCCCUGCGGGCAGCCGUGCCGAGAUGAACCCCAGUGCCCCCAGCUACCCCAUGGCCUCGCUCUACGUGGGGGACCUCCACCCCGACGUGACCGAGGCGAUGCUCUACGAGAAGUUCAGCCCGGCCGGGCCCAUCCUCUCCAUCCGGGUCUGCAGGGACAUGAUCACCCGCCGCUCCUUGGGCUACGCGUAUGUGAACUUCCAGCAGCCGGCGGACGCGGAGCGUGCUUUGGACACCAUGAAUUUUGAUGUUAUAAAGGGCAAGCCAGUACGCAUCAUGUGGUCUCAGCGUGAUCCAUCACUUCGCAAAAGUGGAGUAGGCAACAUAUUCAUUAAAAAUCUGGACAAAUCCAUUGAUAAUAAAGCACUGUAUGAUACAUUUUCUGCUUUUGGUAACAUCCUUUCAUGUAAGGUGGUUUGUGAUGAAAAUGGUUCCAAGGGCUAUGGAUUUGUACACUUUGAGACGCAGGAAGCAGCUGAAAGAGCUAUUGAAAAAAUGAAUGGAAUGCUCCUAAAUGAUCGCAAAGUAUUUGUUGGACGAUUUAAGUCUCGUAAAGAACGAGAAGCUGAACUUGGAGCUAGGGCAAAAGAAUUCACCAAUGUUUACAUCAAGAAUUUUGGAGAAGACAUGGAUGAUGAGCGCCUUAAGGAUCUCUUUGGCAAGUUUGGGCCUGCCUUAAGUGUGAAAGUAAUGACUGAUGAAAGUGGAAAAUCCAAAGGAUUUGGAUUUGUAAGCUUUGAAAGGCAUGAAGAUGCACAGAAAGCUGUGGAUGAGAUGAACGGAAAGGAGCUCAAUGGAAAACAAAUUUAUGUUGGUCGAGCUCAGAAAAAGGUGGAACGGCAGACGGAACUUAAGCGCAAAUUUGAACAGAUGAAACAAGAUAGGAUCACCAGAUACCAGGGUGUUAAUCUUUAUGUGAAAAAUCUUGAUGAUGGUAUUGAUGAUGAACGUCUCCGGAAAGAGUUUUCUCCAUUUGGUACAAUCACUAGUGCAAAGGUUAUGAUGGAGGGUGGUCGCAGCAAAGGGUUUGGUUUUGUAUGUUUCUCCUCCCCAGAAGAAGCCACUAAAGCAGUUACAGAAAUGAACGGUAGAAUUGUGGCCACAAAGCCAUUGUAUGUAGCUUUAGCUCAGCGCAAAGAAGAGCGCCAGGCUCACCUCACUAACCAGUAUAUGCAGAGAAUGGCAAGUGUACGAGCUGUUCCCAACCCUGUAAUCAACCCCUACCAGCCAGCACCUCCUUCAGGUUACUUCAUGGCAGCUAUCCCACAGACUCAGAACCGUGCUGCAUACUAUCCUCCUAGCCAAAUUGCUCAACUAAGACCAAGUCCUCGCUGGACUGCUCAGGGUGCCAGACCUCAUCCAUUCCAAAAUAUGCCCGGUGCUAUCCGCCCAGCUGCUCCUAGACCACCAUUUAGUACUAUGAGACCAGCUUCUUCACAGGUUCCACGAGUCAUGUCAACACAGCGUGUUGCUAACACAUCAACACAGACAAUGGGUCCACGUCCUGCAGCUGCAGCCGCUGCAGCUACUCCUGCUGUCCGCACCGUUCCACAGUAUAAAUAUGCUGCAGGAGUUCGCAAUCCUCAGCAACAUCUUAAUGCACAGCCACAAGUUACAAUGCAACAGCCUGCUGUUCAUGUACAAGGUCAGGAACCUUUGACUGCUUCCAUGUUGGCAUCUGCCCCUCCUCAAGAGCAAAAGCAAAUGUUGGGUGAACGGCUGUUUCCUCUUAUUCAAGCCAUGCACCCUACUCUUGCUGGUAAAAUCACUGGCAUGUUGUUGGAGAUUGAUAAUUCAGAACUUCUUCAUAUGCUCGAGUCUCCAGAGUCACUCCGUUCUAAGGUUGAUGAAGCUGUAGCUGUACUACAAGCCCACCAAGCUAAAGAGGCUGCCCAGAAAGCAGUUAACAGUGCCACCGGUGUUCCAACUGUUUAAAGUGAGCUUUUCCCUCUGGUUUGUUGUUUUAAGCUUGUUUUCUUCAUCUUUUAUAAAGUUUGUUGAGCAUAUUUUGAAAUGUACAUAGCAAAAGAUCAUUUUACAGUUCAUUUAAAUGUAUUGCUAAUUUUUCAAGGAAAAGUGGAACUAACUAUAGAGGAAUUAAAGGAAUUUUACCCGUUAACUGUUGGAUUUUUAAAAUCCCAGGACUUUCAGGUGGUGUUUUUUUUUUUUUUUUUUUUUGAGAUGGAGUUUCGUUCUGUCGCCCAACCUGGAGUGCAUUGACGCGAUCUCGGCUCACUGCAACCUCCACCUCCCAGGUUCAAGCAAUUCUCCUGCCUCGGCCUCCCGAGCAGCUGGGAUUAACAGGCCCAUGCCUGCCACCGUGCCCAGCUAAUUUUUGUAUUUUUACUAGACUUGGGGUUUUGCCAUGUUGGCCAGGCUGGUCUGGAACUUCUGACCUCAAGUGAUCCGCCCACCUCGGCCUCCCAAAGUCUUGAAAUUACAGGCGUGAGCCACUGCGCCCUGCCAGAUUUUGUAUAGUAAUAUAUAUAUAAAAUGACCUGUCACAGGUUGGCUUUCAUAGUUUUACCUUUCCUUUUUGGGUGGUGCCCUUGGGUCUCUACUACUGUCUUUCAUCACUCCCAAGAAAUUGAGUAGUGCAGCCAGGAUCAGGACCAGGGAUUGGCAAAUGUUUUUUGUAAAGGGCCAGAUAGGAAAUAUUUUGGGCUUUGAGGACUGUGUUAUCUCUGAAAUGAUCUUGUUCCAGUGUUACCAUGUCAAGACAACCAUAGAUAGUAUGUAUACAAAUGAACAGGUAUGGCUGUGUUCCAGUAAAACUAUGGAUAAAAACAACCACAUUGCAUUUGGCUAAGGGCUUUAAUUUGCUACUGACAAGUGAUAGUCCUGGUCUUAAUUUGUUUUUUUAACAUUUACAGAUUGAUCAGGGACCAUGAAAAGAAACUUGUGCUUCACCGAAGAAAAAUAUCUAAACAUCGAAAAA